ACAAGCCCAGCCCGGGCAAGCGGCCGCCACCUGCCCGGCGCCGCCUCCGCCCGCCCCCACCGCGGCGCAACUUGGAUGGAGUUGGGGUCCUGAGCGCCGGCCCCCCACAGCCGCCAGCGCAGAGCUCGUGCCGCCACCUUCGUUCUGGGACCCCUCUCUCCGCUGCUCUUCGCUCCCGCGAUGGGAAAAGUUGGCGCCGGCGGCGGCUCCCAAGCCCGGCUGAGCGCGCUCCUCGCCGGCGCGGGGCUCUUGAUCCUCUGCGCCCCGGGCGUCUGCGGCGGCGGCUCCUGCUGCCCCUCGCCGCACCCCAGCUCCGCUCCACGCUCGGCCUCGACCCCUAGGGGCUUUUCCCACCAGGGGCGGCCAGGCAGGGCUCCUGCCACGCCCCUGCCCCUCGUAGUGCGUCCCCUGUUCUCAGUGGCCCCCGGGGACCGAGCGCUAUCCCUGGAGCGGGCUCGGGGCACUGGGGCAUCCAUGGCGGUUGCUGCACGCUCCGGCCGGAGGAGACGGAGCGGAGCGGAUCAGGAGAAGGCAGAACGGGGAGAGGGCGCGAGUCGGAGCCCCCGGGGAGUGCUAAGAGAUGGAGGGCAGCAGGAGCCUGGGACUCGGGAGCGGGACCCGGACAAAGCCACCCGCUUCCGGAUGGAGGAGCUGAGACUGACCAGCACCACGUUUGCGCUGACGGGAGACUCAGCACACAACCAAGCCAUGGUCCACUGGUCUGGCCACAACAGCAGCGUGAUUCUCAUUUUGACAAAGCUCUAUGACUAUAACCUGGGGAGCAUCACAGAGAGCUCGCUUUGGAGGUCAACCGAUUAUGGAACAACCUAUGAGAAGCUGAAUGAUAAAGUUGGUUUGAAAACCAUUUUGAGCUAUCUCUAUGUGUGUCCUACCAACAAGCGUAAGAUAAUGUUACUCACAGACCCGGAGAUUGAGAGCAGUUUAUUGAUCAGCUCAGAUGAAGGGGCAACUUAUCAAAAGUACCGGCUGAACUUCUACAUUCAAAGCUUGCUUUUUCACCCCAAACAAGAAGACUGGAUUCUGGCAUACAGUCAAGACCAAAAGUUAUACAGCUCUGCUGAAUUUGGGAGAAGAUGGCAGCUUAUCCAAGAAGGGGUUGUACCAAACAGGUUCUACUGGUCUGUGAUGGGGUCAAAUAAAGAACCAGACCUUGUGCAUCUUGAGGCCAGAACUGUGGAUGGUCAUUCACAUUAUCUAACUUGCCGAAUGCAGAACUGUACAGAGGCCAACAGGAAUCAGCCUUUUCCAGGCUACAUUGACCCAGACUCUUUGAUUGUUCAGGAUCAUUAUGUGUUUGUUCAGCUGACAUCAGGAGGGCGGCCACAUUACUACGUGUCCUACCGAAGGAAUGCAUUUGCCCAAAUGAAGCUUCCGAAAUAUGCUUUGCCCAAGGACAUGCAUGUUAUCAGCACCGAUGAGAAUCAGGUGUUCGCAGCGGUCCAAGAAUGGAACCAGAAUGACACGUACAACCUCUACAUCUCAGACACACGUGGUGUCUACUUCACCCUGGCCUUGGAGAAUGUCCAGAGCAGCAGAGGCCCUGAGGGCAACAUCAUGAUCGACCUCUAUGAGGUAGCAGGGAUAAAGGGAAUGUUCUUGGCUAACAAGAAGAUUGACAACCAAGUGAAGACUUUCAUCACAUAUAACAAAGGCAGAGACUGGCGUUUGCUGCAGGCGCCGGACACGGAUCUAAGGGGGGACCCCGUGCACUGCUUGCUGCCCUAUUGCUCACUACACCUUCACCUGAAGGUCUCUGAGAAUCCCUACACAUCAGGGAUCAUUGCCAGCAAAGACACAGCUCCAAGCAUCAUAGUGGCAUCAGGUAAUAUAGGUUCUGAAUUGUCAGACACUGACAUCAGCAUGUUUGUCUCUUCAGAUGCAGGGAACACCUGGAGACAGAUCUUUGAAGAAGAGCACAGUGUUUUGUACCUGGAUCAAGGUGGAGUCCUGGUUGCUAUGAAACACACAUCUCUCCCAAUUCGACAUCUUUGGUUGAGUUUUGAUGAAGGGAGAUCUUGGAGCAAAUACAGUUUCACAUCUAUUCCACUUUUUGUGGAUGGGGUUCUGGGUGAGCCUGGAGAAGAGACUCUCAUCAUGACAGUGUUUGGACACUUCAGCCACCGCUCUGAAUGGCAGCUGGUCAAAGUAGAUUACAAGUCCAUUUUUGAUAGACGGUGUGCCGAAGAGGACUACAGACCUUGGCAGCUGCACAGCCAGGGGGAAGCAUGUAUCAUGGGAGCAAAAAGGAUAUAUAAGAAGCGAAAAUCAGAGCGGAAGUGUAUGCAAGGAAAAUAUGCAGGAGCUAUGGAAUCUGAACCCUGUGUCUGCACUGAGGCUGAUUUUGAUUGCGACUAUGGUUAUGAGCGACACAGCAAUGGCCAGUGCCUGCCGGCAUUUUGGUUCAAUCCAUCCUCUCUGUCAAAGGAUUGCAGCUUGGGACAGAGUUACCUCAAUAGUACUGGGUACAGGAAGGUGGUUUCCAAUAAUUGCACUGAUGGCGUAAGGGAACAGUACACUGCCAAACCGCAGAAGUGCCCAGGGAAAGCCCCGCGGGGGCUGCGGAUAGUCACGGCUGAUGGAAAGCUGACAGCGGAACAAGGACACAACGUCACUCUCAUGGUGCAAUUAGAAGAGGGUGAUGUUCAGCGGACACUCAUCCAAGUGGACUUUGGCGAUGGUAUCGCGGUGUCUUACGUCAAUCUCAGCUCCAUGGAAGAUGGGAUCAAACACGUCUAUCAGAACGUGGGCAUUUUCCGUGUGACCGUGCAGGUGGACAACAGUCUGGGUUCUGACAGCGCCGUCCUGUACUUACAUGUAACUUGUCCCUUGGAGCACGUGCACCUGUCUCUUCCCUUUGUCACCACAAAGAACAAAGAGGUCAAUGCGACGGCAGUGCUGUGGCCCAGCCAAGUGGGCACCCUCACUUACGUGUGGUGGUACGGAAACAACACGGAGCCUUUGAUCACCUUGGAGGGAAGCAUAUCCUUCAGAUUUACUUCAGAAGGAAUGAAUACCAUCACAGUGCAGGUCUCAGCUGGGAAUGCCAUCCUACAAGACACAAAGACCAUCGCAGUAUAUGAGGAAUUCCGGUCUCUUCGCUUGUCCUUUUCUCCAAACCUGGAUGACUACAACCCGGACAUCCCUGAGUGGAGGAGGGACAUCGGUCGAGUCAUCAAAAAAUCCCUGGUGGAAGCCACAGGGGUUCCAGGCCAGCACAUCCUGGUGGCGGUGCUCCCUGGCUUACCCACCACUGCUGAACUCUUUGUCCUACCCUAUCAGGAUCCAGCUGGAGAAAACAAAAGGUCAACUGAUGACCUGGAGCAGAUAUCAGAAUUGCUGAUCCACACGCUCAACCAAAACUCAGUACACUUCGAGCUGAAGCCAGGAGUCCGAGUCCUUGUCCAUGCUGCUCACUUAACAGCGGGUGUAAUAAAAAGAUGUUAUCACAGAGAUAUUAGAGAAUUAAUAUUUCCAGGCUUCAGUUGCUACCACUGGAUGUGUUAUGAGUAAAUUUGGGAGGGAAUAAGAAACUUCAAAUUUCGACCUAGGUCGUGAUACAUCAUGAAUUCUGCACUACAAUUUCACAUUGAGAAAAAGACUUUCCACUUGAAGGGAGAAUUACCGUUCGUCAAGAAGUUUUAGAAACUACAAUAUAAUCUCAGCCACAACAUUAUGGAUGCAGAUGCCAAAUAGGAGUUGUGGAACUCUGAACUGUAAAGUGAAGUAAAUUGUUGCAAUAACAUUUUCCAUUUAGGGAUGAAAUUAGUACUGGUGAAAUUCUUCCACAGCCAGUAAGUUUAUCUGUCUCUUUAGUUUUCGGUCACCGUAUUAUCUACAUAGUAAUCAUUUACAAGUCUUUUUUAAGUAAAGCCUUGGUACCGAUAUGUUUUCUUCCUUUUAUUUUUCCCCAAAAUAAAUAUAUUUUUUAUCUUCAAGUAAUUAGGUAGUUGCACAGAUACAUAGACCCAGCGGCUUUUCAUAGUUAUUUAAUCAUUAUGGUGUUAUAAACAAUAGUGGGUUUAUCAUGUAGAUAUAUAUCUAAAUAUAUCCCUCCCCGCAAUAUGAUUAAAUGUGAUAUUUUCAUCUACCUACCAGCGUGCAGCAAUGAGGUUGCUCGUUGGCUUCGUUUAGACACAGAAUCUAGUUCUGUUUUCCAGUCUGGAGGGCAGGGGCACAUCAUAGCUCACUACAGCCUUGAACACCUGGGCUCAAGCGAUCUGUCUGCCUCAGCCUCUCGAGUAGCUAGGACUACAGGCACGCACCACCACAUCCAAUUAAUAUUUUUAUUUUCUGUAGAGACAGGGUGUUGCUAUGUUGCCCAGGCUGAUCUCAAACUCUUGGCCUCAGGAGAUUCACCCACUUCAGCCUCUCAAAGCAUUGAGAUUGCAGGCAUGAGCCACCAUGCCUGGCCUAGCUUCUAAUAAAUUCUUUCUUCACCAUUUCUUUUUUUCUGAGAUUACGGGGGACCGUAAAAGGGGCUGAAAUGAUUACAGGGUAACUAGACUGAGUUAGCCAGGCUAGAGGAUAUGUCUGGAAACUCUUGGUCAGAGAAUGGUCAGCAAGGAACAGUCAGAUGAACAGAAACAGGGGCACAAACAUGCGUCAGAAAUGCAGUAUCCCAGGGGAAGGCAAGGCAGAUAGUCAAGAGAAAUUAGCAAAAAGAAAAAAAAAAAGUAAAGCAAAGGGGAAGGAUAACACAUAUAAAAUACAGACAAGAUGCCAGAACAUAGGACAAGCUACCCUUUAGACACCAAGUUUCUGAUACCUAGAGUGAUCAGGACUGUCCUGGGUUAUCUAUGCUAUAUCAGCGUAAGCUUUAAUAGCGCCCCCUUUCAUUCUUAAAGUGUCUUAUCUUUGAAAAUAAUAUGUAUGGUCUUCUUACUUUUACCCUGCCACCCUGAGAGUGGGGAUAGAAGACUAUACCAAAAAUUGGCUAAUGUGGAGCUCAAAGGUAAUAAUUGGUAAUUGAAUGUUUAACCAGUUGAAAGAGACUUUUGAGGAAAGUAAAUAAGCUAUUGCUAUGUAACAAACCACCUAGAAGUUCAGUGGCUUAAUAGUAAGCAUUUAUUUUUGCUUAUGCGUCUAGUCUUAUCUACAUUCACUUGUCUGUCUGCAAUCAGCUAUGGGUUGUUGGUUGGGGAGCUCUGCUGAUCUUGGCUGGUCUGUCUCACAUGUUACGGGUCAGCUGCCUGCAGGCUGCUCUAGCAUGCUUUGGUUGGAAUAAUUAACCUGGCCUCUACAUGGCCUUUCAUCCUUUGACUGUUCUGGUCUUGCUCACACAUGGCAGUGGUAGGAUUCCAAGAGAAAAAGCAGAGGUAUGCAAGGCCGUGAAAUUCACAAUUAGCACACCAUUGCUUCCAUUGCAUUCCAUUGCCAGAUGCAGAUUAUAAUAAUAGCUCAGAUUCAAGACAUGAAGAAACAGAUUUUACCUCUUGCCUUUUAGGUGAGACAAGCUUCAAACUCAUUGCACAAAGUUUAGACACAGAGAAGGGUAGAGGAUUGAGCCAGCAAUGUAAUCCAUAUCUACAUGAGGCUGACUGCUCACUUAGGGGAGACUUGAGAUGCUUUUAGGUAGUUUAACAAACUUUCUUCUGGAGCCAUCACCAGAUUGAGCUACUAUCAACAGCAAAGGGGAACAUUUGUGUGUGUAGGGGGGUAUUUUUGCUUUGUUUUAGUGAUCCAGAAAAUAUAAAAGUCAGGCAUGCCCUAAAGACAGGACUGGAAGUUUUAUGAGUGAGAAUAUCUGGGGCCUGCUAUGCGGUAUUCUCAAACUGUUAUACAUAAUAAUUACCUGGGUACCUUGUCACAUAUAUGGAUUUUGGAGACCUACUCUCAAAGACUAUACAUUUUUUUUUUUUUUUGAGACAGAGUCUCACUCUGUUGCCUAGGCUGGAGUACAGUGGCACGAUCUUGGCUCACUGCAAGCUCCACCUCCCGGGUUCAUGCCAUUCUCCUGCCUCAACCUCCCGAGUAGCUGGGACUACAGGUGCCUGCCACCAUGCCUGGCUAAUUUUUUUUGGACUAUACAUGUUUUUUUUUCAAGUGAAGCCUAGCUAACAAUAUUUUCACAAGUGCUCCAAGUAAUUCUGAUUCAGGUAGUCCAUAAGCUACACUUUGAGGAAUAUUUCACAUAGUAGCCAGGAAUCAUCACCUUCCAACCUUAGAAAACCAUAAGUCAUUCUUCUCCUCUUGUCUGUUUAUUAUGAUGAUGGUUGGUCUUGGAGUUACUGAUGUUUGUCAUUACUUGGCUAAGUGACCUCAACUCCCUGUCACUGGAUAUUACUGAAGAUUCACCCUCAGUUUAAAUUCAGAAACAAUGCUUCACUUGUCAUUAGAGCUACUAAAGGACAAACUGAGACACAUUAAAAUGUUAAAGAGUUUAUUUGGGCAAACAAUGAUUCAUUAAUCAGUUAGCACUAGACCACAGUUGAUUUAGGGCUCCCUAAAAGGCAUGAGGCUUUUAUGGGGUGAAGGUGAAAGCUAGGCAAAGAAAAUAUUUGAUCGGUUAAAAUGGAGGAAUAGCCUUCUUUGGAUAAUUCUAGUAGAAAGUCUCUCAUUAGAUAUUAGCUAGUGGUUUCUAAUUGAUUAAGCUUAAGUUUUGUUUUCCUAGAAUAUGACUGUUUACUCUUUACUUGGGUUUUGGUUUGGUUACAUAGGAACCCAGGACGCCAGAGCUGCCUCAGUCUAAUGGCCUCCCAAUUGGCUACUUUAACAAGAGACUUCCCUGGAAAUUCCCACCUAGUCUAGUCUGCAGUCUUGUGGCUUUUUCCCAAUAACAUAGGAAACUUUAAGACUCUGAUGAUUGGAUUUGUUUCUAAAUGGAGGGAAGGCCCAUUGGACAACUGAAAGUGCUCUGUAAAUGGAAGCCUUUCUGCCUAUUCUGCAUUCUGGAUAAACUUUCUCUGUGCUAUUCCCAUAUCACUGUAAUUUCUGAAAAAAUAUUUCAGACCACAUGGAUUUUGUGAUAUUCAAAGCAUAUAACUCAAGCCUGAAUUGAGUCUACUUUGGGGUCAGGAGAGGAAAAAAGAAUAUCAAGGUAUGGUAAAUUACUUCUACAACAUCCUGAAAACACUAACUCUUGGAUUAGAAUUAGAGUUGAAAGUUUCGGGGUCAUAGUGCAAGUAGCAGUUCUCCAGGAAUGUCCUUUUGAUAGAAUGAAAGUGAACACUGGACAACAAUAAGAUUGUUCUGCAUGGCUUCACUGGGUGAUGCUACCAUGUUAUUGACCUUAAAACUUGGAAAGAAACCGAGCAAAGGGCAAAACUGCAGCAAGGGGGACCGGGUGCAAUGGCUCACACCUGUAAUCCCAGCACUUUGGGAGGUCAAGGCGGGUGGAUCACUCAAGGUUAGCGUUCGAGACCAGCCUGGCCAACAUGGUGAAACCCCAUCUCUACUAAAAGUACAAAAAAAAAAAUUAGCCAUGCGUGGUGGCAGGUGCCUGUAAUCUCAGCUACUCGAGAGGCUGAGGCAAGAGAAUUGAUUGAACACAGGAGAAGAUUGCAGUGAAUCGAGAUUGUGUCACUGUACUCCAGUCUGGGUGACAAAGCAAGACUUCAUCUAAAAACAAAACAAAACAAAACGAAAAAACUGCAGCAACAGGGAAAGCAGUGCCUGGGGAGAGGCAUUUCCUAGAGUGUUAUGUGGAACCUAGUUCUGCAAAGGGUCUGUGGUCAAAUGAGUUUAUGAAAGACUAUGGUAAAGUUAAAUGUGUUCUUUUCUGCAAGGGCUGCUGUGAUCAUUUAAUAUACUGAUGUGCAUUGUGAAUCUCCAUAUGGGGAAUGUUGUAUGUAUCAUUGCCCCAAAUUAUCUCACCAGGGAACUGUCAUCAUUUUUCAGGAUUUUUUUUCUGUAGAAGAAUACACUUUCAGAAAUAUGAUAGCAAUAAUAUGACAAUGUUAGAAAUAUUGGGCAUGUAGUCUGUCCCAAAUACUAUGACAGUACUUUAUAAAUUCCAUCUCAUUUUAAUCUCACAAAUUUCUAGACUAAACACUAGUUUCGUCUCCAUUUUGCAGAUGAGGAAACUGAGAUUUAAUUUAAGUCACUUAGUCUAUAAGUGACAGAGCCAGGUUUGAUUCUGAAAAGGGCUCAUAUCAUUACUUAACCCCAAAUGUGGAAUUUUGAAUUUGUUCUCAUACAUACAACUAUAACCAUUUAUUUAGCACUUACUACGUGGCAAUCACUUUUCACAAGAAGAUUGUUGUUAUUAUUGUAAGUGUUCCCAUUAUUAUCGUUCCAGGUCCUCAUGAAUAAAAUAUAAAAAUUCAAUGCAUUUCCAAAUUCCUCAGAGGAUUUUAGAAAUGAUAUGUGCAAGUACGCAGGCUUAAAAAUGUUGAGUCACUUGGAGUACUGCUGGUAUCCAUGUUUUACUUUGUGCAUGAAUAAUGGCAAAAAACUGCUCAGCACUUUCCCCUACACGUCUACCUUGUUUAAGCUGCAACUGGAAAGGGAUUAAAGUAUGCUAAUUCCACACAACAAGCUAAAGCCCAUUUAUCACAAGUUUCCAUCCCUCAGCAAAACACACACAAAUGCACCUAAGUGCUGGGCAAACUAAGAAAUGCAGCUGCUGUUGUAUGGAGCAAUAAUAGGUCCCUUUAUACUCAGGCACCAAUCAGCAAGCAGACACCACCCACGGAACAGAGGGCAGUGGUAGUCAGUCUCUGGCCACUGCUGCUGGCUGCUUCCUGCUUCCUGCUUCCUGCCUCUGAGAAAUGACUGACUGAUGCAGAGAUGGGGAGGGUGAAUGGAUAACACACAUUUUAGAACUGGGAUACAGAAGUUCAUUUUCCCAGAAUAAUAUGCUAAUUACUUAACAGUGUUAAUGCUGCUUGUUGAAGAAUGAUGAUUUAAGUGUAAAUGAUUUAGAAUCGAAAGACAACCUGGGGAUGGGGAGAGAUAGGAGGAAGGAAAGAGAAGGGAAAAGGUUCAUGUGUGUGUGUGUGUGUGUGUAUGUGUUUGUGUGUGUGCAUGCAUGCAUAUGCGAGUUUGCUGUGUUGCUGACAGCUUGGACAAAGUAAUUUUCUCUCAGUUUUCCAUUUAUUUCAAAUGCCAACCUUUUCAAGCAAGCUCAGUAUUCUUAGUUGCUUCAUAUCACUGGUAUUCUGGUUAUGCUGAAAGAGCAUUUAGUUAGGAGUGAAAAGUUUAGCUUUAUUUCAACCUCUAACCAUCCCAAUCAUCUGUGGCCCCUUCCGAGCCUCCAUUGUUCCCUGACAAAUUAAGGGUUUGCAUUAGAAUAUUGCCUUUAAAACAUCUUCCUAAUAUAAUUUCCUUGAUGUGAUGAUGGUAUUGUGGUAAUGAUGAGAGAGAGAGAGAUCUUAUCUUUUAGAGUUAUAGGUGGUUAAAUUAUAAGUUUUCCAAGAUUUAUUUCAAAAUAAUCCAGUGGUUGGAGGUUGUGGGGACUGGAUAAAAUAAGACUGGCUGUUGGUUGAUGGUUGUUGAAGCUGAGUGGUAGGUACAUGAGGCUUCAUUUCUGUAUUCUGUGUGUGUGUGUUUGCAUGCACACAUACAUAUCCAUACAUAUAUAUACACAUAUGCAUAUAUGUAUACACAUACCUGUCUUCCAAACGUAAGCGUACAUGAUUUAUUAUUCCUACUGCUCCUUUUAAAACUUAGUAUUUUAACUUGUGCUCCUUGUUAAUUUGCUUUUUGUGCUAUAGUCUUAGUCCUAAUCCCCAUCCUCAGAAAUAUGUCUUUUACUGAAAUUAGCCCAGGAUUGAGUAUAUAGAAAGUGUGUGUGUGUGUGUGUGUGUGUGUGUGUGUGUGUGUAUGUAUGACGAUUCAGGUUCAAGUCUUGGUUCUUCCAUUUACUAGUAAGUACUAAGUCCUUUUAAAACAACACUAACCAAUGAGAACUUCAUUGUUAUCUGUUUAAUGGGGAUCAUAGUCACUGCCUUCCAUUUGUGAAAAUCAAUUGUGAUAAUGUCUAUGACAAAUGGAAGGUGUUCUCUUCCCCUGAUGACAUCCUACCAGUUGCAGGGUGAGUUCUGAAGAAUUUCUGAACCUCUCUGCCGAUGGCAUUGAGAGCUUUGUUUUCUAAUUUUGAACCAAAAGAAAAUUUGCCUUGGGCGUUCCACGGCAGUGGGACCCCACCCAUCUUUUACACACAAACCUACAUAUUCCCAUUUCAAAACUGAGGUGAAGUUUGACUUACAGGGGAGAGAAAAUAGCGGGGGGGUUCCUUAUAUUCAGUGCCUCCUGAAAGCCAACUCUCCUGAAAUGACUAUUUUCUGAGAAGGAAGGGGUGGCUUUCAUUUUUCACCAAAACUAUGUGGUUAGAUGGAAUAUGCUUCCCAGUAUCAAUACAGAGUGGCCGAGAUGUAAUCCUGAAAAGAGUAGACAGAGCAGAAGCAACUGAGAGUCUUGUCUGAGACCAUCAGUAUUAUAGUCACUUAUUCUUGAACUUUUUUACCUGGGUGAUUAGAAUGUUGCCCUCUCGGCUCACACCAGAGAAAACCACAGAAAAUGGUGAUUAAAGGUCACCUGUAUUUCUGGGUAUCAGGCUUUGCUUAAGUUGAUGGAAGGUAAAGGUCAGCACCAAGGCUUCCCUGGAGUACAUGUGGCUUGUCUUUUAUGCACGAGCUGCACUACAUUUGCAAAAUGUCAACUUUUAAGAGGGUAGAAAUUAAUUGCAAAGUCUACAGGUACAACAGGUUUGACUGUGAGAUGGGGGAAGGUGGAGAGGUGGCGAGAAGUGUUUUCCAGACUGCACCUCAAGGGGAAACUCAGGGAGGGAGACUCUUUCAUGGAGGCAGAGGCUUCUGUUUUGUCUGAGAGAAAAACUCACUGUGUUUGAGAGGCUGGAGCAUCUUGGGGAGGGCUGUCAGAGCUUUUGGGAGAUUGUGGAGACAGCCAGGUGGCAUAUCCCUCCUUCAGCAUCUCCGCGGCUACCCUCGUGAAAUACUCACUUGGCCAUCAGUUUCCUGUGUACAAAAAUACAAGCAUGCUCCAUCACUUUGCUGUUCUUUCUCUCACGUAUGACAACUUUCCAAUUAUUUUUCUCACAUGACAACUACUGGAGUAGGGGUGACGGGGUGGUUGAAUUCACAAAUGUAUUCCUGCAGGUGGUUUUAUUGGCAAUCUGUUUUGCUUUGUGGAAAAAGCUUACACUCAGAGUAUAAUAAAAUAUAAUUAUUAUAUUAUAAAUAUUGAUUAAUAAUACUAAUACUAGCAGCAGUAGAAAUGAAAUCUAAUAGGUACAUGACUUACUAUGUGCCUGGCACUUUUCUCAAUGCGUAACAUACAUUAGCUCACUUAAUCCUCAUAAGAACCCAAUGAAGUAUAUACCAUUAUUUUUAUUUUACCACAUAAGGUACAUUAAGGUGAAGCAAAUUGCCCAAGACCACAUAGCUAGUUAGAGUGGGACCUGAAUCCAGACAGCCUGGCCCUGGGGUCUGUGCUUUUCAUUGCUCUGCUGCAGAGCAGGAACAUUUGGGGUGGGAGUAGGGGUGGGCUCAGAUGCAUCCCAUGUCAGCCAUGUGACAUGCAUCUUGUGUGUAUAUCCCACAUGGUUUUCCAGGACUUACCUCUGCUUGUGUGUGAAACAUUUGAGCCUCUCAUAGAGUCUCACCUGCCCAGUUCUCUGCUCAUUUUUCUCUGCUCUGUUUCCCC